GUACUCUGAUUGGUGACGGGUGAGGCGGCCCGAAAUCGUAGGACUUCCGAAAGCAGCGGCGGUGUUUGCUUCACUGCUUGGAAGUGUGAGUGCGCGAAGAUGCGAAAGGUGGUUUUGAUCACCGGGGCUAGCAGUGGCAUUGGCCUGGCCCUCUGCAAGCGGCUGCUGGCGGAAGAUGAUGAGCUUCAUCUGUGUUUGGCGUGCAGGAACAUGAGCAAGGCAGAAGCUGUCUGUGCUGCUCUGCUGGCCUCUCACCCCACUGCUGAGGUCACCAUUGUCCAGGUGGAUGUCAGCAACCUGCAGUCGGUCUUCCGGGCCUCCAAGGAACUUAAGCAAAGGUUUCAGAGAUUAGACUGUAUAUAUCUAAAUGCUGGGAUCAUGCCUAAUCCACAACUAAAUAUCAAAGCACUUUUCUUUGGCCUCUUUUCAAGAAAAGUGAUUCAUAUGUUCUCCACAGCUGAAGGCCUGCUGACCCAGGGUGAUAAGAUCACUGCUGAUGGACUUCAGGAGGUGUUUGAGACCAAUGUCUUUGGCCAUUUUAUCCUGAUUCGGGAACUGGAGCCUCUCCUCUGUCACAGUGACAAUCCAUCUCAGCUCAUCUGGACAUCAUCUCGCAGUGCAAGGAAAUCUAAUUUCAGCCUCGAGGACUUCCAGCACAGCAAAGGCAAGGAACCCUACAGCUCUUCCAAAUAUGCCACUGACCUUUUGAGUGUGGCUUUGAACAGGAACUUCAACCAGCAGGGUCUCUAUUCCAAUGUGGCCUGUCCAGGUACAGCAUUGACCAAUUUGACAUAUGGAAUUCUGCCUCCGUUUAUAUGGACGCUGUUGAUGCCGGCAAUAUUGCUACUUCGCUUUUUUGCAAAUGCAUUCACUUUGACACCAUAUAAUGGAACAGAAGCUCUGGUAUGGCUUUUCCACCAAAAGCCUGAAUCUCUCAAUCCUCUGAUCAAAUAUCUGAGUGCCACCACUGGCUUUGGAAGAAAUUACAUUAUGACCCAGAAGAUGGACCUAGAUGAAGACACUGCUGAAAAAUUUUAUCAAAAGUUACUGGAACUGGAAAAGCACAUUAGGGUCACUAUUCAAAAAACAGAUAAUCAGGCCAGGCUCAGUGGCUCAUGCCUAUAAUUCCAGCACUUUGGGAGGCCAAGGCAGAAGGAUCACUUGAGACCAGGAGUUCAAGACCAGCCUGAGAAACAUAGUGAGCCCUUGUCUCUACAAAAAGAAAUAAAAAUAAUAGCUGGGUGUGGUGGCAUGCGCAUGUAGUCCCAGCUACUCAGAAGGAUGAGGUGGGAGGAUCUCUUGAGGCUGGGAGGCAGAGGUUGCAGUGAGCUGAGAUUGUGCCACUGCACUCCAGCCUGGGUGACAGCGAGACCCUGUCUCAAAAUAUGUAUAUAUUUAAUAUAUAUAUAAAACCAGAGCUGACAAUGACACUCUGGAACAUUGCAUACCUUCUGUACAUUCUGGGGUACAUGGAUUUCUACUGAGUUGGAUAAUAUGCAUUUGUAAUAAACUAUGAACUAUGACUGUC